AGCGGCUGGUCGGCGGCAGCUCUGCUGGUGCGGGGGCGGCGAGCCCGGGAUCGAGCUACCGCGGCCGAGCGCGCCGGCCACCGCCUGCACCGCCCUUCCGCCCGCCCUCCGGACGGCCGCAGCCCUGCGGGUCUCCGCUCCAGACCCACCCCCGCCCCACCCCGCGCGCCUCUGCCGCCUCUUCCAGAGACCCAGCUUGCCGAGCGGCCGCCGCUGCCGCUGUCGCCGCCGCCGCCGCCACCGCGCCAGGUUCCGGCCGCGGCCACCCUCCGCCGUCCAGGGCCCCUCCGUCUCGGCCCCGGGACCCCGGCUCCCCGCCAGCCCCGGCCCCGGCCCCGGCACCAUGUCGGAGAAAAGCGUGGAGGCAGCGGCCGAGUUGAGCGCCAAGGACCUGAAGGAGAAGAAGGAGAAGGUGGAGGAGAAGGCAAGCCGGAAAGAGCGAAAGAAAGAAGUGGUGGAGGCUCCAGUCCCAUUGGUGGUGAUGGUGGGCAAGGCAUGCAGCCAGCCUGAGGCUACUCCCUCUCCUGGUCCCCACAGGAGGAGGAGAACGGGGCUGAGGAGGAAGAAGAAGAAACUGCCGAGGAUGGAGAGGAGGAAGAUGAAGGGGAAGAAGAAGAUGAGGAAGAAGAAGAAGAGGAUGAUGAAGGGCCCGCGCUGAAGAGAGCUGCCGAAGAGGAGGAUGAAGCGGAUCCCAAACGGCAGAAGACAGAAAAUGGGGCAUCGGCGUGAGCCCCUGCCAACAGGCUGGGGUUGGGAGGCCUCUCUGGGCCUGGAGGUGGGGGUGGGGGCAGCCAAGUCCAGCCACUCUUCACCUGGCUCCCUGCUCUGGGCCCUGCACCAGAGCUGCCACCCUCUUCUUUCUCCCCAGCCUUCUCAUUUCCGCCUCUCCAGACACUGCGCCCUCCACCCUCACUCUGCCAUUGUUCCACCUCCUGACCUGCUCCAUCUGAGCUCUCCAGCUGGCCCCCAAUUGCUCCUCUCUCUCUUUGCUCUCUUUCUCCCUCCCCUACCAGCCUCAUUCUUCCUCCGGUAGCCUCUCCCACCUAACCUCUGCAUCCCCCAGCCUCAUGUCCUGCCCCAUCCCUAUCCUGCCUGAUCCCUGGAUCUCCCUCAGAUCCCCUCUUCUCAGACAGCGCCAGGCCGGGGUGGGGCCGGGGUUGGGGCCGAGCCCCACAGCUGCCCCCCUCCCCUCCCUUUUUGUAUAAUUUAAUAAAGAAAUGGUCGCGCUUCUGUUUUUAA